GUGGUAAAAGGCCGGUACCUCGGGCAAGAUGGCUAUCAAGAGUAUCGCUUCCCGCCUCCGGGGUUCCCGUCGUUUUCUGAGCGGCUUCGUGGCUGGGGCUGUAGUGGGCGCUGCGGGAGCUGGGCUCGCGGCCCUGCAGUUCUUCCGGAGUCAGGGCGCUGAGGGAGCGUUGACAGGGAAGCAGCCGGAUGGUAAGUCUGUGGGCCCGUCCUCCCUUCGCUGGCCCAGAUUUCGGGCUCCGACUCCUACCUGGAGUGUGAAUGGCAGUCCUUGACGGACAGCCUUCACCGUUUGCUGGGCCCCUAGCCUGGCCCUUGGUUUCUGACCUUUAUUCUCCCGGCUCGGCCUCCCUUCCCCACCUCGCGUCUCGCCAGCUUCCCUCAUGUCCUUCCUUCCCCCGGGCAUCUUCGUUUUCUGCACAGAACCACCCCCGCCGCCCGACUUUCUUCCCCCCAGUUACUCAUCGCGAUAUCUAUGUUUUAAUGUCUGUGUUCUCUACUAAGAUUGUUAGCUCCAUAAGACUUGAGACUAUGUCUGUUUUGGUCUCCAUCAUCUAACCAGCACAGUACCUGGUACAUAAUUGGCAUUCAGAUCUGCAGAAAAGGCUGUCUUGGAACAAUUUGGAUUCCCUUUAACUGGAACAGAGGCAAGGGAACUAAAAGAGUGCCAGUAGAUGAAUGAGGGGGAAGGUGAUGUGAAAUGAUGCUGGAGAAGUAAGCAGGUGUGUCAGUUUAUUCAUGUGUCCUUAUGUCUUGAUAGGGUCCUGUAGAAUUGCCAGAUCUUGAUAAUUAAUGUCAAAUUGGUUUCUAGGUAGAUUCUUCAAGUUUACACUCCUAGCAUCAUUGUUUCUUCUCUCUCUCAACCUUCACCUAUGGUGAGCAUUACUGAGCUUUACCAAUUUAAUGCUCAUUUUACUUGUGUUUAUUGAUUAUCAAUGAGGGUUAACAUGCUGUGAAUUAGUCUUUUUUGGUAAGUUAUUCUUUACCUAUUUCAGUUGGGGUAUUCUCUUUUGAAUUUAUUUGUAAAAGUUCUUUUAUUUAUUAAGGAUAUUACCUUUUGUCACAGUUGUUUUGUUCCCUUUUGUUAUUUGCUUUUUAAUUUGCUGUGUGUUCCACAUAUUCUCCUUUGCUUUAAAAUGUGUGCUAUGGCUAUGCAUAUUAAAAUGCUGAUAUUAAAGUUAGUGUGUGCCAUUCUAGAGUGCACAGCAACCAGCAGAAUAACAGGAGGCUUGGAAUGUACUUGGUGUUAGACAGAAACUGAUGUAAGUGAAAACUUUAUCAAGCAUAUAAGAAAACCUGGGCAUUUUAUAUUGUAUAAUAAGUCUUGUGAGCUGUGUACUUUUGAGGCAAUAAAAUAGAGCCAAUUAAUAUUAUUUGAAAAUAGGGAGCAAUGUACCUGUGUUUUACUUGAUUUUAAUGUAAAAGGUCUUCUGUUUUCAGUAAUGAUGGACUGAGUUAUUCAGAUAGAAUCUUCCUGCUGAAACAGAAAAUGUUAGUAUAUAAAAAGUGUAUAUCUGUAUUUUUUUUACCUUUUUUUUUGAGAUGGAUUUUUGCUAUGUUGCCUAGGCUGGUCUUGAAUUUCUGGGUUCAAGUGACCCUCCUGCCUCAGCCUCCUGAGUAGCUGGGAUUACAGGUAUGUGCCACUAUGCCCAACUAAAAGUAUAUCUUUUAAAAAAUGGCUUAAGAAAAAUGAAGAGCCAGCAGCAUAGUGGCGAAUUGCUAGGUUAGUGUUGGUGGGAGAAAGCGAGAAUCCAAAGAGGUAAGCGCAGUCUUGGCAAACCAAAACCACAUUUGCCUUUGAAUUCACAGCAUUAUGGGGUGAGGAGGAUUGAAGGAAAGACCUAAGACUCACCCAAGGUAGAUUGUCCUGUAGGUCUUGCAGUGUAGGAGACCCUUCCUGUGUUACCCUGGAACUCCAAAGGGCUACAUCCUCAGGGAAGAGUGAACUAGAACUAACUUCCCUGCCCACUCUUAGGGACUACAUGGAAGGUUGUCUUGGCACUGAACGGAGAAAGGUCAAAAGGAAGAUAAAAAGUUUGUUCCAGAGAAGGUAAAGUCAAAAACUGGCUAUCAUGCAGACUUACAGCCCAAAUCUGUGCAUCGAGAGGAGAUCAGGGAACCUUAAUCCCUGAGCAUGGUUUAAUACGGUUCUCCACUGGGAAUACUGCUAGACACCUUACAGCAGUAAAUUUAUAUCUUUUCUCAAGGAAGGUAUCUUUUUAGGUCUUUGGAAAUUCCUACAAAUUGCUUUUCCAGGGCAGUAAGCACCAGCCAAAGAUAACUAGCUGUAGAAGGAAGUGAUUCCAAUGGUAAUGACACUUAGAAAUUUACUAAUGAUAAAUUUUUCUGUAUUAUUCUUUAUAAAGUGAUUCUAAAAAGCUACAUAUAUGAUACUUUACUGUAAACUUUGGGAUCUGAUACUAAAUUUUUCUUGGCUGAAUGAAAUCACCUUGGAAUCAGUGACUUCAUUGUUCUCCAUUUUACACUUCUUUGAAUAACAGUCUGAGUAUGUUUCAUUUGUUGUCAUAACUUUUGUAGUUUAAGAAAGUCUCACCUCACGAUAGUGCAAUAGGUAGUGUUAGGAUUUGCUAAUGUUCUCUGUGACAAACCAUUCUGGAGGUGUCAGAAAAUAAAUAAAAUCUGAGAUUUCUUCUCUCCUAUGUGGUACCCAGAUAUUCUGUUUUAGAAAUUUCUGGGUGGAGCUCAUAACUUAAAUGUUUAUUUUGUCAUGGUUCGAGAGGCAGUAAGCAAGAUAUCAGAGACACUCCUCUCCCCAAGGCUGUGCUUGCCUAGAACAAAUUGUUUUGUGUCUAUAUAUAUCCAUUAUUUCAGUACACAUAAACUUGUCAAAUACAAUCGUACAAAAUACAAUACAUGGGAGUCUUUUUUAAAAAACAAGAGUUUAUUUAGUAGCCAAGCUUUUUAUAUAGUUUAGUGUUUUGAUUGGUGAUUGUUUUUACUUAAAAUACUAUUCAGAGGAGUUUUUCUUUAACUGGAAAGGCCAGAGUCAAAAUUAUAUGAGAUAGCUACACUGUAUGAAAAGCAUUCUUUCCUAGACUAGUACUUUCUAAAUUCAGAUGAAGUAUCUGAACUAUCCCAGGAACUUGAGACAUGCAUGCAAUCCCUAAUACUAGCUGCUUGGAGAGACACCAGCCAGUAGCAACCAGCUUGCCUUGCUUAGAGAAUCUUGAGGGACAUUUGUCUACUGAUAACAUAUCCAUUUUGUGUGUUUUUCUUCAGGUGAUGCAGACAGAAAGCAUUGUAAAUUUAAGCCUGAUCCCAAUAUCCCUCCAACCUUCAGUGCCUUCAAUGAAGAUUAUGUUGGAAGUGGGUGGUCACGAGGACACAUGGCUCCAGCAGGAAAUAACAAAUUUUCAAGUAAAGCCAUGGCUGAAACCUUUUACCUUUCUAACAUUGUGCCUCAGGAUUUUGAUAAUAAUUCUGGAUAUUGGAACAGAAUAGAAAUGUACUGUCGAGAGCUGACAGAAAGGUUUGAAGAUGUUUGGGUGGUAUCUGGGCCUUUGACCUUACCUCAGACUAGAGGCGAUGGAAAGAAAAUAGUUAGUUACCAGGUGAUUGGCGAGGACAACGUGGCAGUCCCCUCACACCUUUAUAAGGUAAUCCUGGCCCGCAGAAGCUCAGUAUCUACCGAACCACUGGCGCUAGGGGCCUUUGUGGUACCCAAUGAAGCCAUCGGCUUCCAGCCCCAGUUAACUGAAUUCCAAGUGAGCCUCCAGGACCUAGAGAAGUUGUCAGGACUGGUGUUUUUUCCUCAUUUGGAUAGAACUAGUGAUAUCCGGAAUAUCUGCUCUGUGGACACCUGUAAGCUCCUGGAUUUCCAGGAGUUCACCUUGUACUUGAGUACAAGAAAGAUUGAAGGAGCCCGAUCAGUGCUCAGACUGGAAAAGAUCAUGGAAAACUUGAAGAAUGCAGAGAUUGAACCAGAUGAUUACUUUAUGAGUCGCUAUGAGAAGAAGCUAGAAGAACUCAAAGCUAAGGAGCAGUCAGGAACCCAGAUAAGAAAGCCAUCCUAGUUUUUAUCUCAAGAUGUGUCAUACCGUCUGUAAUGAAGCAGGCAUGCCCUCUUUAGGCUAACAUAUUUUAGUGGCUUUGCUUUUUGCUUUUUAAAAAGUUUUUCUCUUUAAGAGAUGUGGUCUCGCCGUGUCAUCCAGGCUGGAGUGCAGUGGUGGAAUCAUAGCUCACUAUAGCCUCAAACUUCUGGGCUUAAGCAAUCCUCCUGCCUCUGCCCCCUGAGCAGCUGGGACUACAGGCACACACCAUCACCCUCAGCUACUAGUGGCUUUGCUUUAAAGAAACAGUGGAAUCCUAAAUUUAUGACUAAAAAUUCCCCCAAAAGAUGAAAGAUCUACAAUGUUUUUGUCAGUAUUAUAUUUGACUCAGGAACUAAUUAUUAAGGGAGCUUUGACACCUGCAGAUGGAGGGCUGAUCUUGUGUCAAGUUAACAGGAAGACUGCCCACAGAUGACACUGCAUUUGUAUCCCUGUGGAUGUAGAGUAUUGGGAAGGCAUUUGUUUAGUUUCAUGCCUCCAAACCAUGCAUUGUCUGUGAUGUAUCUGCCCAGCCUUCUCAGAACUCAAUGUUGUACAUUUUUCCCUCUAGGACCUGAAUUGGUCUUGGAGGCAGCUUUUAGAAAUCCUCUGUGUAGUUCCUGUCCACAUGCACUAUAUAUUUGUUUCUUUUUUCUCCUCUCAUGAAUCUGCUCGUUUCUCUACUUCUGUCUACGUAGAAGCACUCAGCAACUAGUUUCUGCUCAUUAAAUGUGUUCUAUAUACUAGGCUCAGUGCUUUACAUGUGUUGUCUCACAAUGACUCUCUGAGGUAAAUACACUAUCCCCAUUUUACCUGUGAGAAAAUUGAGGCUUAGAGAGCUUAGUGUCUUACCUGAGUUUCACUUUUCCAAAGUAGUCAUCCACAAAGUAUGAGGCAGACAGAUCUAAGAGAAGAAAGACAGCUGAGGUAGAUUCAAAUCUUUUCUGACAUGGAUGGUGGCUUUUUACUCAGAAAUAUAUACCUAUUUCCAUGGGUAUUUGUGGGCCUGAGGCAUGCUUGGCAAGAAGAGUCUGGUUUCUCGUCUGCUAUGCAAGCCAAAGGGACUUUAAUGUUCUUUGAAUUGAACCCUCCUUAGCUCUGUGGAAAGAGACAGUCAGGAAUAUUUGGGAAUUAGACGGCAAUACUUUGUGGGGUUUAUUAGAGCCCAUGCUUGCCUCCAGAGAUACAGUUCUUUUAGUGACCAGAUACUGCCAAAUUGAUGUGUUCUUGCUUUCCAGGUGAGCUUUUUGUUCUUAAGAUUAAGAAACCUAUGAAGGAUCUGCAGCCAGGCAUGGUGGCUCAGGCCUAUAAUCUCAGCACUUUGGGAAAUCGAGGUGGGUGGAUCGCUUGAGCCCAGGAGUUUGAGACCAGCCUGGGCAACAUAAUGAAACCCUAUCUUUACAAAAAAAUACAAAAAUUAGCUGGGCGUGGUGGUGCACACCUGUAGUCCCAGCUACUCGGGAGGCUGAAAUGGGAGGAUUGCUUGAGCCUGGCAGGUCAAGGCUGCGAUGGGACAUGGUCAUGCCACUGGACGCCAGCCUGGGCCACAGAGGGAGACCCUGUCUCAAAAAAAGAAAAGAAAAAAGAAAAAGGUCUGCCCACAAAAUCACUAGCUUAUUAUUUGCUUCCUGUGUGCCUGCUUGUCUACCUAGCAUAGUAGGCCAAAGGUCCAAAGGCAUUUAGCAUUCCUAGGGGAAAUUGUGGCUGUUUUUCUGAGCCAGAUCUCUUGAUUUGGGUUUACACGGAGUCCUUUCAUGGACUAUCCUGAGUAUUGUCAGUAAAACGUCUUGGGGCAUAAGAACUUGUCUGAAUCUGUCAUACAUACCACUGCUGUCUUUUCCGAGUGGUAUUACAAGAAAGAUUUUUGUGGUGUGUUUGUUCUAAGAGAAAUGCCAAGGCUUUCAGAUAAAGAUAAGAUGAUAAUGA